AUUCCUGAGGAGGACUGCCGGUCGUUCGGACGUCUUGCCUGUCGCUGGAGGAGAGGUCCGGGCUCUCCAGGAAGGUGGCUGCGGCGACAAAAUGAAGAUAUUCGUGGGCAACGUCGACGGGGCGGAUACGACUCCGGAGGAGCUGGCAGCCCUCUUUGCGCCCUACGGCACGGUCAUGAGCUGCGCCGUCAUGAAACAGUUCGCCUUCGUGCACAUGCGCGAGAACGCGGGCGCGCUGCGCGCCAUCGAAGCCCUGCACGGCCACGAGCUGCGGCCGGGGCGCGCGCUCGUGGUGGAGAUGUCGCGCCCAAGGCCUCUUAAUACUUGGAAGAUUUUCGUGGGCAAUGUGUCGGCUGCAUGCACGAGCCAGGAACUGCGCAGCCUCUUCGAGCGCCGCGGACGCGUCAUCGAGUGUGACGUGGUGAAAGACUACGCGUUUGUUCACAUGGAGAAGGAAGCAGAUGCCAAAGCCGCAAUCGCGCAGCUCAACGGCAAAGAAGUGAAGGGCAAGCGCAUCAACGUGGAACUCUCCACCAAGGGUCAGAAGAAGGGGCCUGGCCUGGCUGUCCAGUCUGGGGACAAGACCAAGAAACCAGGGGCUGGGGAUACGGCCUUCCCUGGAACUGGUGGCUUCUCUGCCACCUUCGACUACCAGCAGGCUUUUGGCAACAGCACUGGUGGCUUUGAUGGGCAAGCCCGUCAGCCCACACCACCCUUCUUUGGUCGCGACCGCAGCCCUCUGCGCCGUUCACCUCCCCGAGCCUCUUAUGUGGCUCCUCUGACGGCCCAGCCAGCUACCUACCGGGCCCAGCCGUCCGUGUCACUGGGAGCUGCCUACAGGGCCCAGCCUUCUGCCUCUUUGGGUGUUGGCUAUCGGACUCAGCCCAUGACAGCCCAGGCAGCCUCUUACCGCGCUCAGCCCUCUGUCUCCCUUGGGGCACCAUACAGGGGCCAGCUGGCUAGUCCUAGCUCCCAGUCUGCUGCAGCUUCUUCACUCGGCCCAUAUGGUGGAGCCCAGCCCUCAGCCUCGGCCCUUUCCUCCUAUGGGGGUCAGGCAGCUGCAGCUUCUUCGCUCAACUCCUAUGGGGCUCAGGGUUCCUCCCUUGCCUCCUAUGGUAACCAGCCAUCCUCUUACGGCGCCCAGGCUGCCUCUUCCUAUGGGGUUCGUGCAGCUGCUUCUUCCUACAACACCCAGGGAGCAGCUUCCUCCUUAGGCUCCUACGGGGCUCAGGCAGCCUCCUAUGGGGCCCAGUCUGCAGCCUCCUCACUAGCUUAUGGAGCCCAGGCAGCUUCAUAUAAUGCCCAGCCCUCGGCCUCUUACAAUGCCCAGUCUGCCCCAUAUGCUGCACAGCAGGCUGCUUCCUACUCUUCCCAACCUGCUGCCUAUGUGGCACAGCCAGCCACAGCUGCUGCCUAUGCCAGCCAGCCAGCAGCCUACGCCGCACAAGCCACUACCCCAAUGGCUGGCUCCUAUGGGGCCCAGCCGGUUGUGCAGACCCAGCUGAAUAGUUACGGGGCCCAAGCAUCAAUGGGCCUUUCAGGCUCCUAUGGGGCUCAGUCGGCUGCUGCGGCCACUGGCUCCUAUGGUGCCGCAGCAGCCUACGGGGCCCAACCUUCUGCCACCCUGGCAGCUCCUUACCGCACUCAGUCAUCAGCCUCAUUGGCUGCUUCCUAUGCUGCCCAGCAGCAUCCCCAGGCUGCUGCCUCCUACCGCGGCCAGCCAGGCAAUGCCUACGAUGGGGCAGGUCAGCCGUCUGCAGCCUACCUGUCCAUGUCCCAGGGGGCCGUUGCCAACGCCAACAGCACCCCGCCGCCCUAUGAGCGUACCCGCCUCUCCCCACCCCGGGCCAGCUACGACGAUCCCUACAAAAAGGCUGUCGCCAUGUCGAAAAGGUAUGGUUCCGACCGGCGUUUAGCCGAGCUCUCUGAUUACCGCCGUUUAUCAGAGUCGCAGCUUUCGUUCCGCCGCUCGCCGACAAAGUCCUCGCUGGAUUACCGUCGCCUGCCCGAUGCCCAUUCCGAUUACGCACGCUAUUCGGGCUCCUAUAAUGAUUACCUGCGGGCGGCUCAGAUGCACUCUGGCUACCAGCGCCGCAUGUAGGGCCAUCCUGGGAUGGGGCACCACAGGGAGGGAGGGAGAAAAGAGGUGGGUAGGGUUACAGAUCCAGGUUAUAACUACUCUGGCCCAUACCUUUCCUGGUUGUGGUUUUUCAUGCCCUCUACCAUGUGGGCCUUCCCCAGGAGAUGAUCCUGUUAAGUGUUCGGCAGUAACCUACUUUGUUCCUUCGCCUCAGCAGCAAAUCUUGCUACUGGCUCUAGAUCUGCGGUUUCCCCUCUACCCUGCCUCCCGUCUCCCCAGAAUGGGAAUUUCUUUUAUGUUUUUAUUUUUUUCCUGGCUCCCUUUUAUUUUUGUGCGCGAUAUUUAAGGUCGUCUGGAUGGGGAAGCAACCUGCAGCUGAGGUCGCCGGCGCCUUUUUCUUUUUAGAUGGGAAGGAGGCCAGGAAAGGGUCAGCUUAACCAUUUCCUAUGUGCCAAGCUGUGCCAGCAGUCCAGGGUACCCUGACUGUCCCUCUGUAGACUGUUGAGACUGAGUUCCUGUUGGGACAGUCAGUUGGUAUGUAUCCAAGUCCCUGCUGACCACUAAUGUUCUAGCUGAUGGUGAGCGGCACAGUCCCACUUCCCCAUCUCCCCAAGUAGGUGGUGUUAGAAAACCUUAAUUUUUUUUCCCUUUUGUAUGGACUACAAAUAAAACUUGGGGCAAUUUGCAGUUUGGAAACCUGGUUGUCAUUGUCUUGAUUGCAUUCAGUGUCAAAGGAGCCAAUUUGACAUCCAGGAAGACAUGAUAGCUAAAGGGAAGGCAGUCAGAGAACCCAGGACUGGUGAGGAAAGGGGUUUGAAUGUCGGAAUUAGAAGGAUUGCCCUGUGGCCCAGAAGGAUUUAGCUCAUCGUCGUCCUGCUAGCCUGCCAUCUUUCAGACUUUCCAGGGCAGGUGGCCUGGUCCUCAGCCCUCAACUUGAGUUAGUCACACCAAAAUGCAGUAAAUGAUGCCCAUUUUCCUCUGCCUGUGCUUGACCAUUUUCACUGACUUUUCUCCAGUUCAGGAAUAACCUGUGUUCCAAUGGGAUGGUUCUGGGGUUUGGCCUCUUAGGAAGUGGGGAAUGGGCUGCUGUGGUAUUUACAGGCUAGUAGAUCCUUUAGGCAGUAGGCUGGAAUGAGUGCUGGGGCUGGGACCCAGAAAGGAACCAGUAGUGGAGUGGGGGUAAUGGCGUUGCCUGAUACUGCCCUAUGGUUGGAAUAAGGAAGGGCAGAGAAAACUUGAAGCAGGUAUGGGGCAUUCUGGCCAUAGAGCUCGUAUUUUGCCUGUUGAGCUGUACCAUGGAGCAUCCUCCUGUGUCCUGCCAACCCCUGCCAUUAUAGUCACCGGAGACUCCUUUACCUAUCCCUAUCUGUUAGGGUUUUCAGAUGUCCUCUCGCUGGGUUUAUAUUUGAAGGUAUAGAAUCUGGGAAAGGGUGGGGUGCAAGCUAACCAAAUAGGGAUGCUAGGGUUGGGUGGGGAAUUGAGGACUCUUCUGUGCUUUUAUUGUAGGGCUGGGGAUCGAGGAUCUGGGCAAAAAAUAUGACAUUUCCAACCAGGGACAAAAUGGAGGCUUGGGCUUAGUGAUGGGUAAAUGGAAGACUGGUUGAGUGGGAUGAUAAUGGGAGAACUUACUGAUGCUCUUUUGGGAAAAGGUGCUUUAAAGACUCGAUUUGGGAGCCUACUGGGGCAAGGCGACUGGGGAGGUGUACGUGUUAGUCAAGUGGAGGUCAGGUGGGUUAUCUUCUGCCUCCUUCACUGGCUUCAUGUGAACUUGCCUGUGACAGAAUAUCUUGCCCUAGAUGUCCUCUUCCCUCUUGCCAUCGUGCAAAAGCAUUCGAUCUUAUGACCGUGAGUUCUUAUUUGUGGAUGCUAACUGGGGUAAUCUCAGGGAGUACUGGGGCCAUGGCUCUUUCCCUUGCUUCUCUUUCUGCUCACUGCUUUGCUUUCAGGUGCUUAGCUGCUCCUUUUUAUUUCUUUGCAGGACUGGGAAAGCAUGGGAGGAGGAUUUUGAUAAGUUUCUUGUUCUCUGCGUGGUGAUGGGGUGGUCUGAGGGCCAAGUUAAUAAGCCUACCUUUGGUUAUUACCCUGGAAAAUUGAGGGUUGAUGGUAGGGUUAUGAUUGUGGCCUGUGUAUUUGCAAUUUUUCUUUGUCAGUGUGGCUUUCUGUCAUCUUCCUUUUUCUCCAGUGAGGGUUCUGCCACUGUCUCAAUCCCUUGGUUCCUGCAAAAAACAGCUAAAUGUGCUCUCAGGGCCAGUGGUGAUGUUCUGUGUUGCAGCCCCAGCUCUUGAAAGUGACCUGGCCCAGAUGAGCUCUGCCUGCUUGUCAUCUUUAGGUCCUGCUGCCCCUGCUGCCUCAGCCCUCAGGCUCCUAACUGCUCAAGCCAGAAGGAGCUACAAAGCCAAAUCAUUUGUCAUUUUUCUCUGGCAGAUUGUUUUAAAAUCUCCCUCCCCUCUUUUAUUUUAAUUAUGCCACCUGUGUUAAUCCUAUAGCCUGCUUCUUUGCUUUGUGGAUUACUGAUUUCAAGUUCUAUAACUUGGGGAAAGUUAGGUUGAGUGAAUGGGAGGACAGACACUGAAUGUGUGUUUUGGAAAAAUGGACUCUCUAUCUUCAGAUUAUUCAGCUUCUCCACCUAUCACCUCUACAACUUGGCCUUCAUUGGAGAAGUUUUAGUUGGCUUAUUCCUGGAACAAGACCACCUAGAGGCUUUUAGCCUUGUCAGCCUGCCCUCUUCUGAGGUUUGGACCUUGUUUUAAAUUGUGUGCAUGGUGGGCUUGAGACUCUCUUGUAAUGGAGGUAAUGGGACUAUCACUGAGGGGUUCAGCCUAUCCAGGUAGGCUACCGUUCUAGUCAUACCCAUCACUUAAAUUCUGCCACAGUCUGCACAGACGGUUGGUCCUCCAGGCAUAUUGUCCUAUUAAGCCAAAUAGGUGGACAUCAUGGGAUGGAUGAGGUCAUCAUGAAAACAGAUUUACUGGAUUUAUGGACCUAGUAUAUACUAUGUAACAGAUGGAAAACUGAAUUUUACAAUCUAUAGGUACCUUUGAAAGGUCAUAAAGGGUAAAAGUCUAUAGUUUUCCAGAAAAUAAUUCUUAAAACUGGGUUUUAUGUCUAGAUUUAAAUCAUGUAUCUGUCUGUAGUGCUUCAAAUGUGGCCAGGUGUGGUAGCUCACACCUGUAAUUCCCAGCGCUUUGGGAAUUUGAGGCAAGAGGAUUGCUAGAGGCCAGGAUUUUGAGACCAGCUUCGGCAAUACGGUGAGACCUUGUCUCUACCAAAAGAAAAGAAAAAAAAAA